AAUUGGGUCCUGGUGGCCGUGACAGCAGCUGUGCCCAGAGCCCAAGGCGCUGGCUGGGAGAUUGUACUGCUAUGGGGAUGCUGGAGGCACGGGGCUGGCGCCCACUAGACUCACUAGAAGCCCAUCUCUCCGGAAGGAUAAGGGGGCAGGAGGGCGGGGCUACAGAGCGGCCCACCCAACCAACACUGGGUCCGAGAUCCAGCAGAUCAGCCAAGGCCAAGUACGGACAGGAACGGACAGGCUGGGCAGGGGGCCCUGAGACUGGCCAGCGACCACAGAUUCCACCUGCUUGGACCGGCCAGGCGGGGGCCCCUGAGACUGCCCAGAGACCAUGGAUUCCGCCUGCUCGCCUCUGCUGCACGCCUCCUCCUGGCAAGUCCCUCAUGCCCCAUAACUAUAUGUGUUGGGGAUACCAGGUGGGGUAUUUAGUGGUAAAGAGAAAAGAGAGAGUUCUGGGCCCCAGGGCUCAGCCAUGGGAGGUCCUUUCCAGCCCACCCUGAGGAGAAGCAGCAGGAAGUCGCCCAAAAAGUGGCACAGAUGGGCCCAGAACCUCUAUGGGGCUGCCCUGGCCCAGCCUCUGCUCAUUUUGAGCCAAGUCCCCUUGCAAGUUGGUUCUUGGCACGGAACACCAGGGCCUCUCUGGGAAGACACAGAAUCAAGGUACUAGGAGACCAGGGCAGAGCACGUGCCGAGGCAGGCAUUUGCUCUUCAGUGUGGAAUCUGAGCCCGACUGUGGGGACACGAACAGGAAACUGUCCCUGCCCCGCAAGGGCUCACAGACAUGGGGAGACAGGACAGCCAGCCAGCCAGCCUGCGGCUCCCUCUGCCCUGUGCAUGCCCUGUGCUAAGCCCCCACUCAGCAAGUCAGGGCUGCCUUUGCUGGGGAGCAGAUCUGCCACUGGCCCACGUGGCUGCUGCAGGAAAUCUGACCUCUCUCUGUGGCACUGCAGCCGGGACAGCAUGGCCAGCUGCUGAAAGGAGUCUGCCCUCUCAGCCCCUCCCCUUCACUGGCUCCACCAGGAGCCGACCAGCAUCUCAGUGAGGAAAUGGAAAGAGGCCACUGUAGAAACCAGCCGGCCUGCAGGACAGGCUUCAGGAUAUGGACCUGGCAUGGGGCUGGGGGUCCCAUUGGGCCCUCCCGGUCAGACACCUGUGCUCAGGGUGUGUGCACUUGGACCUCCCGCCAUCAUAAGGCCUGUCUCCUCAAUAGAAGCAGAAACAAUCAACCACCAGCAGCAGAUGUUUGAGGAAAGCCCUGUGCCUGAGAGACAGAGGCCAGCAGAGGCGGAGACAGGAGGAAGUAUGUGGCAGGGGCGCAGCUCCAGCAGCCAGCGACAGAAAGAAAGAAACUCGCUCCAAAGAAAAUGUAAUCCUUCCUCUCUAAGACAAUAGAAGAUGUUACACCCAUAAAGCAAGAGCAGGAUGCCAGGAAUGAAGAGCAGAGGGCUCUUUGAGGAUAAUGAAAAUGAUAAGACCAGGGGCCAAUAAGAAGUCCAAGUAGAGAAAACCUCACACAGAGAACAAAGUAGGGGAGGAAAGGUAAGGAAUUAGGAGAAAACACCAGAGCUUAAUACUCAUUAGUGGGUAUUCCAAAAAGAGAAAACAGAGUGGAAGAAAUAAUAUGAAAAUCUGCGCAGCCCUAGACAAGAGUGACCGCCUGGCAGGGUUCCACCCAGUGCCUGGCUCAGUGGACUAACAUGGACCCUACGGGGGCACAUCAGCACGACAAUCAGAGCUCCCAGGCUGGCUCAGUGAACGAACACGGACCCUACCGAGGCACAUCAGCAAGACAGCCAGAGCUCCCAGGCUCCAGCAGGUGCGCCAGACCCUCAGUGGGGCCAGGGAGAACCACACACCGGUUGUGAUCCGAGAAAGAGAUCGGGACAUUGGGGCCCUUCCCCAGCAACUCUGACAACAAGGGAAGGGCGCUGCCCGACUCUGGGAGAAAACCAUCUACAGUGGGAAUGCUCAUCUCCUCACCAGUCAGGGGAGAGGAAGAAACAAGACAUUUUCAGGCAGUCCAAAAGAUGGCUCCCAUGUGGCUUCCUGGGACAGUGCCUGGGGAUGUCCUUCAGGGCAAUGAGGGCCGGGAGCAGGACCCCACAGCCGCCCAGCAUGGCCCAGCGGCACUCAGACAGCUCCUUGGAGGAGAAGCUCCUGGGACACCGCUUCCACUCGGAGCUCCGGCUCGAUGCCGGGGGGAACCCAGCCUCCGGGCUCCCAAUGGUCCGUGGCUCCCCGCGUGUUAGAGACGAUGCCGCCUUCCAGCCCCAGGUCCCGGCACCCCCACAGCCUCGGCCCCCGGGGCACGAGGAGCCAUGGCCCAUCGUCCUGAGCACAGAGAGCCCGGCGGCCCUCAAGCUGGGCACCCAACAGCUGAUCCCUAAGAGCCUGGCUGUGGCCAGCAAGGCAAAGACCCCAGCCCGCCACCAGAGCUUCGGGGCGGCUGUACUUAGCAGGGAGGCCGCCCGGCGGGACCCUAAGCUCCUCCCAGCCCCCAGCUUCUCCCUGGAUGACAUGGACGUGGACAAGGACCCCGGGGGCAUGCUGAGGCGGAACCUGCGGAACCAAUCCUACCGGGCGGCCAUGAAGGGCCUGGGGAAGCCAGGUGGCCAGGGAGAUGCCAUCCAGCUAAGCCCUAAGCUCCAGGCUCUGGCUGAGGAACCCAGCCAGCCUCAUACUCGGAGCCCGGCCAAAAACAAGAAGACGCUGGGGAGGAAACGUGGGCACAAGGGUUCCUUCAAGGACGACCCCCAGCUCUACCAGGAGAUCCAGGAGCGGGGCCUGAACACCAGCCAGGAGUCUGAUGACGACAUCCUCGAUGAGUCCUCCAGCCCCGAGGGAACCCAGAAGGUGGACGCCACCAUUGUGGUCAAGAGCUACCGGCCCGCCCAGGUCACCUGGAGCCAGCUCCCAGAGGUGGUGGAAUUGGGCAUCCUGGACCAGCUCUCCACUGAGGAGCGGAAAAGGCAGGAGGCCAUGUUCGAGAUCCUCACGUCGGAGUUCUCCUACCAGCACAGCCUGAGCAUCCUGGUGGAGGAGUUCCUGCAGUCCAAGGAGCUGCGGGCGACCGUGACCCAGAUGGAGCACCACCACCUCUUCUCCAACAUCCUGGAUGUCCUGGGUGCCAGUCAGAGGUUCUUCGAGGACCUGGAGCAGCGGCACAAGGCCCAGGUGCUGGUCGAGGACAUCAGUGACAUCCUGGAGGAGCACGCUGAGAAGCACUUCCACCCCUACAUCGCCUACUGCUCCAACGAGGUCUACCAACAGCGCACGCUGCAGAAGCUGAUAAGCAGCAACGCCGCCUUCCGAGAGGCCCUGAGAGAGAUUGAGAGGCGGCCGGCGUGCGGGGGCCUGCCCAUGCUCUCCUUCCUGAUCCUCCCCAUGCAGCGGGUGACCCGGCUGCCCCUCCUGAUGGAUACGCUCUGCCUCAAGACCCAGGGCCACUCCGAAAGGUACAAGGCUGCCAGCCGUGCACUGAAGGCCAUCAGCAAGCUGGUGAGGCAGUGCAACGAGGGGGCCCACAGGAUGGAGCGCAUGGAGCAGAUGUACACGCUGCACACACAGCUGGACUUCAGCAAGGUCAAGUCCCUCCCACUGAUCUCUGCCUCCCGGUGGCUGCUGAAGCGCGGAGAGCUGUUCUUAGUGGAAGAAACCGGACUUUUUCGAAAAAUUGCCAGCCGGCCAACGUGCUACCUUUUCCUGUUCAACGAUGUCCUGGUUGUGACCAAGAAGAAGAGCGAGGAGAGCUACAUGGUCCAGGACUACGCCCAGAUGAACCACAUCCAGGUGGAGAAGAUAGAGCCGUCUGAGCUCCCUCUGCCCGGGGGCGGCAACCGUAGCUCCUCCGUGCCCCACCCCUUCCAGGUGACCCUGCUUCGCAACAGCGAGGGCCGCCAGGAGCAGCUCCUGCUCUCCUCGGACUCCGCGAGUGACCGGGCACGGUGGAUCGUGGCGCUCACACACAGUGAGAGACAGUGGCAGGGCCUCUCCAGCAAAGGAGACCUGCCCCAGGUGGAGAUCACCAAGGCCUUCUUCGCGAAGCAAGCAGACGAGGUCACACUGCAGCAGGCGGACGUGGUCCUGGUUCUGCAGCAGGAGGAUGGGUGGCUCUAUGGCGAGAGGCUCCGGGACGGAGAGACGGGAUGGUUCCCCGAGGACUUUGCCCGCUUCAUCACCAGCCGUGUGGCCGUGGAGGGCAAUGUCCGCAGGAUGGAGCGUCUGCGGGUGGAGACGGACGUGUAGCCCUGGCGAGGCCAGCCGGCGGCAGCACAGCCUGUCUCCAAUCAGCAAGUGGUCGUGCCUGGCUCUAGAGAGCGUGGGGAGCUGGUCUCAAGGACCCAGCAUGGUUCCCUGGGGCUUCCCAAGAGCCUGUGGCUGUGGUGCCGGGCUCCAGACACUUCACGGAAGGAAGAUCACAUGUCCCCAGAGAGGCACCCCCAGGCAAGCUCGAGGGGGCCACACCGUGUCCCAGGGAGCCCAGCCUAUUCCCGUUGGCUGGCUGGGCCCCUCAGCUGCUGGGCCCCACCUCCCCACUGCACCCAGGGGGCAACUCCACCUGGACUGAUGGGCACAGGAGGCACCAAUAGCGAUUAUUGGGGGCAAUGCGAGGUCUCCUCCUAUGCCCUUCCUACCCCUGAGUGGGACAAGAAGGGCCCUGAGUGCCCAGGAGUGCCCCACGUUCUGAGAAGGGGCCGGCCGGAGGGAGGGGACCCGGCAGGGAGAUUUCGGUUUUGAGGUUUCUAAAUACAUUAAAGUUAUUUCUUAAGAA